CAUUCCACUGGCCCUUGAUUUGCAGACUCUCCUUUCCUAUAGCUCCUGGACAUAAUUUCCUGACACUCUGAACAGCUUGGAUUCGGUGAAAAGCCACAAGCCCCAGCAUGAGUACAGUGAUGUUCCUCCCCAACUCCGCCCUGCAUGGUCUGGUUGGUCAUUGUGCCAACCCACCUGAGAUCCUUUCAGCAGACAGCACGUGGAAGUCCUCCUGCCCCAGGAAACAGGGGUGUGAUGUGGUUGCAAGGGGAGGGCAGGCAUAGGAAGAACUGAGAUUGCUGGACUGGAGAAGGAAUACUUUGAAGAUUGUCCCACUGCAACUCAGAGGAGAAUGGAGUGGAGGUGCUGAGAGAGGCCGUCUCCAUGGGAGCAAGACCACAUGACCACGUGAGCUGAGGGAGUAGCUGGUCAUGCAGAACUGCUGUGGCUCCCAAAGAGUUUUCCAGUUCUGGCUCCAGUCCAUCUGCAUCCCCACACUAAAGCUCUUUGUUUGUUUGUUUGUUUAUAGCCUGAAGAGGGCCAGACCAAGACCGAGACUUGGAGACCUGAUUGAGAUUUCUCGCUUUGGCUAUGCACACUGGGCCAUCUACGUGGGAGAUGGCUAUGUGGUCCAUCUGGCUCCGGCAAGUGAAAUUGCUGGAGCUGGUGCGGCCAGUGUCCUGUCUGCCCUGACCAACAAAGCCAUAGUGAAGAAGGAACUGCUGUCUGUGGUGGCUGGGGGAGACAACUACAGGGUCAAUAACAAGCACGAUGACAGAUACACACCACUGCCUUCCAACAAAAUCGUCAAGCGGGCAGAGGAGUUGGUGGGGCAGGAGUUGCCUUAUUCGCUGACCAGUGACAACUGCGAGCACUUCGUGAACCAUCUGCGCUAUGGCGUCUCCCGCAGUGACCAGGUCACUGGUGCAGUCACGACAGUAGGUGUGGCAGCAGGCCUGCUGGCUGCCGCAAGCCUUGUGGGGAUCCUGCUGGCCAGAAGCAAGCGGGAAAGGCAAUAAAUCCAAGAAAUUGUCCCAACAACCACCAAUUCUUACGGAGGAAUAUUAUUUAGCCAGCAGGAGUGGAGUUUGGUUUACUGAUUUUACUGUUUUGUGUUCAUGAAUCUUUAUUUUAAUGGAGUUAAAAGCACAGGAAAAUGUAUUUGGAAAUGCAGCUUAGUAUGAAUUCUAUUAAAGACACAAUUGGGCUCUGC